AGAGGUCUCUGGCUGGCGGGCGCCCCGUCGGCCGCCGGCUUCCUCCUUGAAACCCGCCGGCGCACAUGAGGCCGCUGCCCCCGCCGCAGGCGCUGGCGGCCCCCUCGCGGUGCCCGUGGUGAUGCCAUGCCCCGCCACCACGCGGGAGGAGAGGAGGGCGGCGCCGCCGGGCUCUGGGUGAAGAGCGGCGCAGCGGCGGCGGCGGCGGGCGGGGGGCGCUUGGGCAGCGGCAUGAAGGAUGUGGAGUCCGGCCGGGGCAGGGUGCUGCUGAACUCGGCAGCCGCCAGGGGCGACGGCCUGCUACUGCUGGGCACCCGCGCGGCCACGCUCGGUGGCGGCGGCGGUGGCCUGAGGGAGAGCCGCCGGGGCAAGCAGGGGGCCCGGAUGAGCCUGCUGGGGAAGCCGCUCUCUUACACGAGUAGCCAGAGCUGCCGGCGCAACGUCAAGUACCGGCGGGUGCAGAACUACCUGUACAACGUGCUGGAGAGACCCCGCGGCUGGGCGUUCAUCUACCACGCUUUCGUUUUUCUCCUUGUCUUUGGUUGCUUGAUUUUGUCAGUGUUUUCUACCAUCCCUGAGCACACAAAAUUGGCCUCAAGUUGCCUCUUGAUCCUGGAGUUCGUGAUGAUUGUCGUCUUUGGUUUGGAGUUCAUCAUUCGAAUCUGGUCUGCGGGUUGCUGUUGUCGAUAUAGAGGAUGGCAAGGAAGACUGAGGUUUGCUCGAAAGCCCUUCUGUGUUAUAGAUACCAUUGUUCUUAUCGCUUCAAUAGCAGUUGUUUCUGCAAAAACUCAGGGUAAUAUUUUUGCCACGUCUGCACUCAGAAGUCUCCGUUUCCUACAGAUCCUCCGCAUGGUGCGCAUGGACCGAAGGGGAGGCACUUGGAAAUUACUGGGUUCAGUGGUUUAUGCUCACAGCAAGGAAUUAAUCACAGCUUGGUACAUAGGAUUUUUGGUUCUUAUUUUUUCGUCUUUCCUUGUCUAUCUGGUGGAAAAGGAUGCCAAUAAAGAGUUUUCUACAUAUGCAGAUGCUCUCUGGUGGGGCACAAUUACAUUGACAACUAUUGGCUAUGGAGACAAAACUCCCCUAACUUGGCUGGGAAGAUUGCUUUCUGCAGGCUUUGCACUCCUUGGCAUUUCUUUCUUUGCACUUCCUGCCGGCAUUCUUGGCUCAGGUUUUGCAUUAAAAGUACAAGAACAACACCGCCAGAAACACUUUGAGAAAAGAAGGAACCCAGCUGCCAACCUCAUUCAGUGUGUUUGGCGUAGUUACGCAGCUGAUGAGAAAUCUGUUUCCAUUGCAACCUGGAAGCCACACUUGAAGGCCUUGCACACCUGCAGCCCUACCAAGAAAGAACAAGGGGAAGCAUCAAGCAGUAAGUUCUGUAGUAAUAAGCAGAAGCUCUUCAGAAUGUACACCUCACGGAAGCAGAGUCAGAAGCUAAGUUUUAAGGAGCGAGUGCGCAUGGCUAGCCCCAGGGGCCAGAGUAUUAAGAGCCGACAAGCCUCAGUAGGUGACAGGAGGUCCCCAAGCACCGACAUCACAGCCGAGGGCAGUCCCACCAAAGUGCAGAAGAGCUGGAGCUUCAACGACCGAACCCGCUUCCGGCCCUCGCUGCGCCUCAAAAGUUCUCAGCCAAAACCAGUGAUAGAUGCUGACACAGCCCUUGGCACUGAUGAUGUAUAUGAUGAAAAAGGAUGCCAGUGUGAUGUAUCAGUGGAAGACCUCACCCCACCACUUAAAACUGUCAUUCGAGCUAUCAGAAUUAUGAAAUUUCAUGUUGCAAAACGGAAGUUUAAGGAAACAUUACGUCCAUAUGAUGUAAAAGAUGUCAUUGAACAAUAUUCUGCUGGUCAUCUGGACAUGUUGUGUAGAAUUAAAAGCCUUCAAACACGUGUUGAUCAAAUUCUUGGAAAAGGGCAAAUCACAUCAGAUAAGAAGAGCCGAGAGAAAAUAACAGCAGAACAUGAGACCACAGACGAUCUCAGUAUGCUCGGUCGGGUGGUCAAGGUUGAAAAACAGGUACAGUCCAUAGAAUCCAAGCUGGACUGCCUACUAGACAUCUAUCAACAGGUCCUUCGGAAAGGCUCUGCCUCAGCCCUCGCUUUGGCUUCAUUCCAGAUCCCACCUUUUGAAUGUGAACAGACAUCUGACUAUCAAAGCCCUGUGGAUAGCAAAGAUCUUUCGGGUUCCGCACAAAACAGUGGCUGCUUAUCCAGAUCAACUAGUGCCAACAUCUCGAGAGGCCUGCAGUUCAUUCUGACGCCAAAUGAGUUCAGUGCCCAGACUUUCUACGCGCUUAGCCCUACUAUGCACAGUCAAGCAACACAGGUGCCAAUUAGUCAAAGCGAUGGCUCAGCAGUGGCAGCCACCAACACCAUUGCAAACCAAAUAAAUACGGCACCCAAGCCAGCAGCCCCAACAACUUUACAGAUCCCACCUCCUCUCCCAGCCAUCAAGCAUCUGCCCAGGCCAGAAACUCUGCACCCUAACCCUGCAGGCUUACAGGAAAGCAUUUCUGACGUCACCACCUGCCUUGUUGCCUCCAAGGAAAAUGUUCAGGUUGCACAGUCAAAUCUCACCAAGGACCGUUCUAUGAGGAAAAGCUUUGACAUGGGAGGAGAAACUCUGUUGUCUGUCUGUCCCAUGGUGCCGAAGGACUUGGGCAAAUCUUUGUCUGUGCAAAACCUGAUCAGGUCGACCGAGGAACUGAAUAUACAACUUUCAGGGAGUGAGUCAAGUGGCUCCAGAGGCAGCCAAGAUUUUUACCCCAAAUGGAGGGAAUCCAAAUUGUUUAUAACUGAUGAAGAGGUGGGUCCCGAAGAGACAGAGACAGACACUUUUGAUGCCGCACCGCAGCCUGCCAGGGAAGCUGCCUUUGCAUCAGACUCUCUAAGGACUGGAAGGUCACGAUCAUCUCAGAGCAUUUGUAAGGCAGGAGAAAGUACAGAUGCCCUCAGCUUGCCUCAUGUCAAACUGAAAUAAGUUCUUCAUUUUCUUUCCAGGCAUAGCAGUUCUUUAGCCAUACAUAUCAUUGCAUGAACUAUUUCGAAAGCCCUUCUAAAAAGUUGAAAUUGCAAGAAUCGGGAAGAACAUGAAAGGCAGUUUAUAAGCCCGUUACCUUUUAAUUGCAUGAAAAUGCAUGUUUAGGGAUGGCUAAAAUUCCAAGGUGCAUCGACAUUAACCCACUCAUUUAGUAAUGUACCUUGAGUUAAAAAGCCUGAGAAACCAAACACAGCUAAUGCUAUGGGGUGUAUGAAUAUGUCAAGUUUAGGUCAUUUAGAAGAUUUGACACUGUAUUUUGAAAUUAUGGGAGUAAACACCUUCAAAUUUCAGGCAUUUCUGCUUUGUGACUAAAUACAAACUACAUUUUCAAGAUUAGGCCAUAAUGUAUAUUUAAACACAAUGGCUAUCAACAGCUGCUAAUAAGGUAUCAACUAAAGCAGAAUUGGGGAAUAAUAGAAAUGGCUGCUUAUUUCAAGAUAUAUUUGCCAACCCAUUCCUAUUCAGUCAUUUUAUUAUUAAUGUAAUUUGAAUGUCAAUUUGUGUGCUUUUGGUGAUUUAGCGCUGUGGCAAGCAAUUUUGCACAUCAUUUUCAUGUUGUUCUUUAUGACAAGAAUGUUCUUCAAUUAGAAAAUGUGCAAAUAAUGAAAUUCAGGGCCAGUGAGGCAAAUAGACUAUCUGACAUAUUUGACUUUAUGAAAACAUAUUGCCUGAUGGCAGAAUCAACUUUAUAAGUGGUCAACUUCUACACAAGCGUAUGAAAUACUGGUCAGUAGAACAGCCAUUGUGAUUGGACUGGUUUCUCUGCAAUGGCGCCAACCCCAGGCUUGCCAAUACUGCCUAUGUAAAGGGCAAGUGUGAGAAGCUAUUCUCAUUUCGCUGACAUACAGGUAGGACUAUGGGGGAUGGGACAUUUGAGUGGGACUGAGAUAGGAAAGGCUUGAAAAGAACCCAGAAACACCACCAGGAAGUUGGCAAAGUAAAAGAAAAUGACUUCCCCCUCAAAGGGCAAUGAGAGGGAGAGAAACAAACCAAAAUAGAAGAACUAGACUUUUUAGAAAAUGAGUAUUGCUAGGGAAUUCAACUACCUAAUCUUCCCUUAUUCUUAUAUAUAAGCAGAGAAUUUUUGCAAGGUAUUUAUUUUUUAAUAUGCCCUGAAUGUCUUUUGCUAUUAUGUGUACAUUUUGCAUAUGAAAGUCUAAAACGAAACUUCCUUUACUUUUUAUACUGUAGUGAAAAUUUUCUAUUCUUCCCAAGAAUGUUGUCCCAAAUCUGAAAUUACUGGUUCAAUUUCCUGAUAUAAACAUUUACAAUUAGAAGCUAGAUAGUACUGGCAGAGUCUGCAAAUCAGAACACUUAAAUAUAUCAUGGCAGCAAAAAGACCAAGGGAAACAAAAUGACAAAUGUAUUUAUCAGAAAGCAAGCAAUGCUGACUGCUUGUUAGAAACCCAUCUAGCUAUCUUAGGUCACCAGAACUUCAGCCAACGUAAUGACAUUCAAAAAAAAAGGACAUAAGAGAUAGCAUUUCAAUUCAAUUAAACCCUAGCCACAGGAGGACUCAAGAAAGGAAGUUGUUUCCUUGGCAGACAUAAAUGCUGCCUCCAGAAGUACUUCUCCAGCAGCCAAGCAGAAUGAGCAGGGUUAUCAAGUGGAUGUUCAAAGGAAGAAGGAGGCCCUGAACUCCACCAAUCCUCCCCAGCCCUCCCCAACAGGCUUUCUCCAUCAUUGACUCUCCCCUGCUUUUCUUCUUCAUUAACUCCUUAUUCAUUCCCUGCCAGUAUUUUGCUUCUGAACUUCACCAGGCCUUAACCAGCCUCCAUCCCCAGGUCAACCAGUUCUCCGCUUUACCUAAAAUGUGCUUCUCAACCUUUUAGAACCUUGUCCCUUUUGAUAAACAUGGAAAUUUUUAAAGCUUCCUCUUCGCAUCCCACUUGGAUUCUAAGACAAUUAGAAUCAUUUAGAAUCUUUUUGGCUGCUGGAAAUGUAUAGAAGAUAGAGGCUAAAUUUUACACUUCAGUUAAGACAUUGUCAAUCCUUUUAAGCAAUUGUUUUCAUUUUCAAAAUACAGAAUGUUAGUAAAUUAUGAAAAUCAAUUUUUCAUCUUCAUUCAACCUGAAGUUGUGAUUCCCCCUUGCAAGAAUGUUGCAUACACACACACACACACACACACACACACACACACACACACACACACACACACACACACACACCCCUCCACUGACCUAAAGCCAGACACCUGCCGUGACUGGGCAGGCUCUCUCCCAUUAUUAACAGAGGAAGAGGAGGGAGGCAGCAACUUUCAGGUAGCACUGAUUCUUGGACAUACUCUGUCCUGGGUCAAACCCCACUGGCAGCAGGAAUUCUGAAUGUAUUGGGGACCCCUCCUUAGGCCUCGUUAAGUCUCAAACACAGUACAGCUCACCCAGCAUUGCUGACGACUGAAGAUUCAGAAACAAAACCUACACACAGCACUGAGGUCUUAAUCAUAGCAAAAUGUGAUAAACCAUGUUGUGAAAAACUUUUAUACAUUGAAGCCAUGACCAUUUUGUGUCUAUCUUACUCUAGCACAAAAAUUGGGGGAUGUUAAAAGAUAGUUGUGUGGAAGCUAUAAGGUUCUGUCUGUCGUGUUACUCUCUGUGGAAAUGAGAGGGGUCUCCCAUUUACACUAAGCAAAUUUCCAUUGGUCAAUUUUAAUGAUGUCUUGAAGCACAAUUUAGCUGAGCACUGAGUAGCCAUAUGCUUUCUGAGUACAAGUGUGUCUGCCUUCUUCAACAUGUAGGGUUGAUCAAGCUAAUACUUAAUUGCAAAUAUCCCUUGUAUGAGGUUAACUAAAAAAAUUUUGCUAUGUCUGAUCUACAUGUUUGCAUUUUGUUCAACUAAAUUAAUAUUUGUAGAUUGCAAGUUUUGUUUAAAAUAACUUUAUUGAGUUUUUAAGUCCUGAUCUGUUCUAAGGUGCCUUUCUCACCUCCCAUUGAUUCAGUGAUUCUGAAGUUCUUAAUUUGCAAGUAAAAUAAGUCUACUAGAGAGGAGGAAAUCAGGCACAAAUUGACCAAUUCUCAUGCCAUUUGCAAAGCAAAACUGUAAGGAUGAUGAAACCUGGCUAACUAAAUUAAUGGAUCAUUUCACUAAAUCAGAUAGAGGAAAUAUCAUAAAUAUUAACUUGUCUCCCUAGAAGCUGAGAUUUUUCGCCUUAAAUGACAUGGUUGUGUUUUUGUAAGAGAAACUUAAUCUAAUCUAAUAAUGUGCAUUUAAGUAAGCAGUUCUAAGUCAUGUAUGACAAUGCAAUUGUCUGUUUCCUGAAAACAAAUAAAUCGGGAACACCAUAUCCAUUUCAAGCUAUCAUUAAAGUGUAAUUUCCUUUGCUCUCUUUUACUGGGAUUAUUUGUUUUAAAGUAAAACAUUAAAAAGAUGUCUAUAAACA